CUCUUCCUCUGCUCCCGCGGGGUCUGUGCUGAGAAUAAUGGCCCGGUUGGCCCGGGACGAGUGGAAUGAUUAAUGAUGUUUUGCAGCAGUUUUCUACGUCUGAAAUUUUUUAUGUCUCUGGAACCCAGAAUUUGCUAAGAGAUGGAGGAACCUCAGAAAAGCUAUGUGAACACAAUGGACCUUGAGAGAGAUGAACCUCUCAAAAGCACCGGCCCUCAGAUUUCUGUUAGUGAAUUUUCUUGCCACUGCUGCUACGACAUCCUGGUUAACCCCACCACCUUGAACUGUGGGCACAGCUUCUGCCGUCACUGCCUUGCUUUAUGGUGGGCAUCUUCAAAGAAAACAGAAUGUCCAGAAUGCAGAGAAAAAUGGGAAGGUUUCCCCAAAGUCAGUAUUCUCCUCAGGGAUGCCAUUGAAAAGUUAUUUCCUGAUGCCAUUAGACUGAGAUUUGAAGACAUUCAGCAGAAUAAUGACAUAGUCCAAAGUCUUGCAGCCUUUCAGAAAUAUGGGAAUGAUCAGAUUCCUUUAGCUCCUAACACAGGCCGAGCGAAUCAGCAGAUGGGAGGGGGAUUCUUUUCCGGUGUGCUCACAGCUUUAACUGGAGUGGCAGUGGUCCUGCUCGUCUAUCACUGGAGCAGCAGGGAAUCUGAACACGACCUCCUGGUCCACAAGGCUGUGGCCAAAUGGACGGCGGAAGAAGUUGUCCUCUGGCUGGAGCAGCUGGGCCCUUGGGCAUCUCUUUACAGGGAAAGGUUUUUAUCUGAACGAGUAAAUGGAAGGUUGCUUUUAACUUUGACAGAGGAAGAAUUUUCCAAGACGCCCUAUACCAUAGAAAACAGCAGCCACAGGAGAGCCAUCCUCAUGGAGCUAGAACGUGUCAAAGCAUUAGGCGUGAAGCCCCCCCAGAAUCUCUGGGAAUAUAAGGCUGUGAACCCAGGCAGGUCCCUGUUCCUGCUAUACGCCCUCAAGAGCUCCCCCAGGCUGAGUCUGCUCUACCUGUACCUGUUUGACUACACCGACACCUUCCUACCUUUCAUCCACACCAUCUGCCCUCUGCAAGAAGACAGCUCUGGGGAGGACAUCGUCACCAAGCUUCUGGAUCUUAAGGAGCCUACGUGGAAGCAGUGGAGAGAGUUCCUGGUCAAAUACUCCUUCCUUCCAUACCAGCUGAUUGCUGAGUUUGCUUGGGACUGGUUGGAGGUCCAUUACUGGACAUCACGGUUUCUCAUCAUCAAUGCUAUGUUACUCUCAGUUCUGGAAUUAUUCUCCUUUUGGAGAAUCUGGUCGAGAAGUGAACUGAAGACCGUGCCUCAGAGGAUGUGGAGCCAUUUCUGGAAAGUAUCAACGCAGGGGCUUUUUGUGGCCAUGUUCUGGCCCCUCAUCCCUCAGUUUGUUUGCAACUGUUUGUUUUACUGGGCCCUGUACUUUAACCCAAUUAUUAACAUUGAUCUUGUGGUCAAGGAACUCCGGCGGCUGGAAACCCAGGUGUUGUGACUGGCACUGCCCAGGCUGAGACUCUUCAAGUCCCGCUGACGUCUGAGCUUUGAUGCUUAAGAGGGGUGAGGCAGGGAGCGGACUUCCUAUUUUCUACCCUCAGUAAAACAAGGUGCUGCUUUGUAUAUCAAAAGCUCCAACCAUGUCCUCUCCCCCUCAGCCUGUGGGUGGCACGAGCAAGGACUGACAUCCGCACAGGGAGGAUUGUCUGUUUGGCUGACACAGCAGCAGCCCUUCCCACCCAGCCACCUUCCUCACAGGGACUAGGAGGCUCAGUCCCCAACGGCUGGCAAGACUCAGGGUCCUCAGUGGACAUGGUGUGGGUGACAUCAGAAGGGUGCCACAUCAGUCCCCUCCCCAACCUCAGUGACUGACAGAGGAUCCGGAUCUCAGAGCCUGAGACCAGGUUUAUUGGGGCCUGGCCUGUCCUCUAAGUCAAGUUUAGGAAAACAAGGAUAAGAUUCUGUCAUAGGCAUAGAGAGUUGCACAUAAAAAAUACCGAAGAAAACCCAAAAUUCAAUCAACAAUUCUGUCUUAUUGAAGAGUUGCUAGGAUUCAGAGUAAAACUCAAAGGAUUCAGUUUGAGCCUAGAAUGAUGGUUAGACUUGUAGUCACUGGGCUUUUGUUUUGCUUUAUGGAAAUCAUUGAAGGUCUGGAUCCCUUUCUCUGAAUGGAGAGAUUGAGAGGGAUGUCGGGCAGUUCCCAUUAGAUUUAGUGGCCUUCAUGUUAUUCAGAAUUGUUUUGGUGAUACCUCACCCCUGUAAUCCCAGCACUUUGGGUGGGUGAGGCAGGCGGAUCACUUGAAGCCAGGACUUCAAGACCAGCUUGGCCAACAUGGUGAAACCUCAUCUCUACUAAAAAUACAAAAAUUAGCCAAGUGUGAUGGCACAUACCUGUAAUCCCAGCUACUUGGAAUUGGAAAUCGCCUGAACCCAGGAGGCGGAGGUUGCAGGGAGGGAGACUGCACCACUGCACUUCAGCCUGGGUGACAGAGGGAGACUCUGUCUUAAAAAAAAAAAAAAAAUCAUCUGUAAAAUAAAUUCCGGGAUAGUCGUUUUGUUCAAGGAAAUGUUUUGUAAAUUGAGCUCACACUAUAUAAUCUUUAUUGUCCUAUCCUGAUGUAUAAUACAGCAGGUAUAAUUACACCAAGCGCUAUAGUUAUAAAUAUGGCAUGAAGUGAACUAUGGCCUUUUAUUUCCUUCCAGUGUGAACACAGCAGGUGUGAGAUGUCAUCUUGGAAGACAGGCCUUGCAGAAAUAGGCCUACAUCCAAAAUAUUAUCUUGUGACUCCAUGAACCAUUCAUUAACCCUUUGUAUCUUUGAGUGAAAAUUUUACUCAAAAGUUGCAUCUGGAAGUUCGAAGAAAUUACUUGAAAUAAAAAUAAAGAUUUCUAUAUAGAUAAAACCUA